AGUCACGUACCCCUGCUUGCUCAAUGGGUCACAACCCUCUCACGCAGACCCCCUUAGUUGUAAAGGGACAGGAAUUGUUCACUCGGGGAGCUCGGUUUUGUAAGUCUGCCGAUGCUCCUGGCAGAAUAAAGCCCUUUCCUUCCUCAACUCGGUGUCUGAGGGGUUUUGUCUGCAGCUAGUCCUGCUACAUUUCUUGGUUCCCUGACCUGGAAGCGAGGUGAUUACCGGGCGGUGGAGGCAACUGCUUAGGAGGCUUAGGCCUGCCUUGUGGAACAUCCCUGCGGGGGACUCCUGCCGGCUUUAGUGAAUCCUGAGAGUGCUUUCAGCUGGGUAAUUGCCCUGGUGGAACGCCUCGCCAGAGCAGCGCACGGUAGGCCCCCGCGGAGGAUUAACGCAGCGGCUGAACAGCGGGAAGGAAUCGGCGCUUGGAGUCCAGACAUCUGGAACACGCUCUUGAACAUCAGAUUCCAGGUUCUGCAGCCUUUGGACUCUUGGACUUAGACCAGUGGUUUGCCGGGGGAUCUCAGAUCUUCAGCCACAUACUGAAGUCUGCACUGUUGGCUUCCCUACUUUUGAGGCUUUGGAACUCUGACUGAGCAACUACUGGCUUCGUUGCUCCUCAGCUUGCAGGUGGCCUAUCGUGGGACUUCACCUUGUGAUCACUUUCUGUCACCCAGGCUGGAGUACAGUGGCACGAUCACAGCUCACUGCACCCUCAACUUCCCAGGCUCAGGUGAUUCUCCUGCAUCAGCCUCCCGAGUAGCUGGGACUACAGGUGUGGACACAUUGAGAAGUCACUAUCUAUGAACUAGGAAGCAGGAUCUCACCAGACAUCGAAUCUGCUGAUGCCUUCAUCUUGGACUUCUCUCUCAGCCUCCAGAACUAUAAUCUGGAGCUUUCAAAAUGUUUGCCAAAGCAACCAGGAAUUUUCUUAGAGAAGUUGAUGCUGAUGGUGACCUGAUUGCAGUAUCAAAUCUGAAUGACUCUGAUAAGUUACAGCUUCUAAGUCUGGUGACAAAAAAGAAGAGAUUCUGGUGCUGGCAGAGACCCAAGUACCAGUUUUUAUCCCUCACCCUUGGCGAUGUACUCAUAGAAGACCAAUUUCCGAGUCCAGUGGUCGUGGAGUCGGACUUUGUGAAAUACGAGGGCAAGUUUGCAAACCACGUGAGUGGAACCCUGGAGACUGCACUGGGGAAGGUCAAGCUGAACCUGGGGGGCAGCAGCCGCGUAGAGAGCCAGUCUUCAUUUGGAACCCUGAGGAAGCAGGAGGUGGAUUUGCAGCAGCUCAUCAGAGACUCUGCCGAGAGAACAAUAAAUCUGAGAAACCCUGUGCUCCAGCAGGUGCUGGAAGGAAGGAAUGAGGUCCUGUGCGUUUUGACACAGAAGAUCACGACGAUGCAGAAGUGUGUGAUCUCUGAGCACAUGCAGGUCGAGGAGAAGUGUGGUGGCAUCGUGGGCAUCCAGACCAAGACGGUGCAGGUGUCAGCGACGGAGGAUGGGAAUGUCACCAAGGACUCCAACGUGGUGCUGGAGAUCCCAGCUGCCACCACCAUUGCCUACGGUGUCAUUGAGUUAUACGUGAAACUGGACGGCCAGUUCGAGUUCUGCCUUCUCCGAGGGAAGCAAGGUGGCUUCGAGAACAAGAAGAGAAUUGACUCUGUCUACCUGGACCCCCUGGUCUUUCGAGAGUUUGCAUUCAUAGACAUGCCAGAUGCUGCGCAUGGGAUAUCUUCCCAGGAUGGACCAUUAAGUGUUUUAAAGCAAGCGACCCUGCUCCUGGAGAGGAAUUUCCAUCCAUUUGCGGAGCUGCCUGAGCCACAACAGACAGCUUUGAGUGACAUCUUCCAGGCGGUCCUAUUUGAUGAUGAACUACUCAUGGUCCUGGAACCAGUGUGCGAUGACCUGGUCAGCGGCCUCUCGCCCACAGUGGCGGUGCUGGGGGAGCUGAAGCCCCGGCAGCAGCAGGACCUUGUGGCCUUCCUGCAGCUGGUGGGGUGCAGCUUACAGGGUGGGUGUCCGGGCCCCGAGGAUGCAGGCAGCAAGCAGCUGUUUAUGACAGCCUACUUCUUGGUCAGUGCCCUCGCAGAAAUGCCAGAUAGCGCAGCAGCUCUGCUGGGCACUUGCUGCAAACUCCAGAUCAUUCCCACACUGUGCCACUUGCUUCGUGCUCUGUCUGAUGAUGGAGUAUCUGAUCUUGAAGACCCAACCUUGACUCCCCUGAAAGAUACAGAAAGGUUUGGGAUUGUGCAGCGCUUGUUUGCCUCAGCUGACAUUAGUCUGGAGAGACUGAAGUCAUCUGUGAAAGCUGUCAUUCUGAAGGACUCUAAAGUCUUCCCACUGCUUCUUUGUAUAACCCUGAAUGGACUCUGUGCUUUAGGCAGAGAACAUUCAUGAUGUCAUAUGUGAACUAGAAGUACGUGUUACUGGCCAAGGCUAUUUUUCAGAACUGUUAAAGGUCAUAUGCACGUUAAAAGUUGACCAAUGAAAUGAAUUUACAGAACAGUUUAAGAAGUGGUGACAUUUUGCAUGAUGAAUGACCUGACUUUUAGCCACCAGGUACUCUUUAAACAGUUUUCCUUAUCAGAGGCCCUCCUGUGCUGGUGACCCAGCAUCUGAGUUAGGUUCCAGCAUGUAAAGAGCUGGGAGGGCGGAGAAUUCUUAGCAUACAUUCAGACGUUUUUUCUGCACAAUAAUAAGUCCAUCUGUCACUUGCAUUCCACUUUUUGUUACAUAGAAAGAGUCUGACCCUUUAAUCCAAAAGGUCUUUUUACAUUGUGAAUGCUGUGGGAAGGCAAUUUCUCUGCACACAAGAGGCUACGUUUUGGAAGUGAUGUAUGUUAUUUGAUGACUGAAAAUGAACUGUAAAUGCUCCUAGAGUAUAUUCCUCUGCUGAACAAAAUUAAACUUCAAAAAAAUCUAACAGUAACACACCCCUGCUUGGGACCCUAGCUAUAUGCAUUUUAUGUGACCUUGCCAUGCUUCAGUGAACAUACUAAUUCUAUGUCUAGCACAUGUUGAUUUCCUAUGUAUUCUGGGUAUUCUAUUAAAGGAAACUUUGAACUAUG